AGGCGGCGGCGGCCACUGGCCAGGCGUGGACGCGCGCGGGGCCGCCGCGGGCACGGAGUGGCCGCCGCGUCGCCUGAGCCCAGAGCCGGGGAGUGCUCUCGGCCGCCGCGUCUCCUGCCCUCUGUCCUUCCAACCCAGCCCUCGGCUGAGCCGCGCCGCACCAUGCCCGCCGUGGACAAGCUCCUGCUAGAGGAGGCGUUGCAGGACAGCCCCCAGGUACCUCCCGCCGCUCCGGUGCCCCUCGCCCGCAGGGGUGAGGCCGAGGAGGCCCCUCCAGCCCCGGAGUGGAGGCCGCGCCCCCGGCCGGGCAGCCGCGGGAGUGCGCCCGGCCCCCUCGCGGCGCCUCCCACCGGGUUCUCUCGGGCUGAGGAGGGGGCGGGCCGGGCCCUGAGUCCUGAGCCGGGGCAGAGCUGUGGAACAGGGGAGAGAGCCCCGCGGCCGGAGUCUUGAUGUCGUGACCCCCCUGCAAGCUCAGCUGCAACUGAGUCUGCGAGAUCUAAACUUUGAUUCCAUGUAGUAGCUGAGUGCCUCAGGAAAACCACCUUAUUGUGCCUUAGUUUUGUCGUCUGUAAAAUAGGAAUAAUAAUUGUGCCUGCUUCAUAGGGUUGUUAGGAGAAGUCAAUGAGAAAUACCUGUAAAGUUGUCAGCAGACAAUGUCCGGUACAGAUAAUGAGUCAGUCUUAUUACUGCUACUCCUAAUGAUGUGAUGAGACUUGUGCCAGCCAGAAUGAGAGGCAGAGGGCCUGGAUCUCUUUUCCGGCGGUACCAGGCCUCCUUUUGGCACCGUUUUCCCAUUAGUGAAGAGAAAAAUACAGUACCUGCCCCAUUUGUCGCACAAGGGAACUUCAUUAGCACACUCGAGAUGAGAGUCAAGUCCUUUGAGCUCUGCAGAUGAAAACUGGUGUGUAAAUAUAGCAAAUGAGUGCAGGAUGACAUUAGUUCAUAAUUCAGCACAUCUUUCCCCAGGGGUCUUUUGUUCUCCUUUGUUUAACAUUUCUCCAGCUUCGUACCUACACUCCUGGUUCAGCAUCCCGGGUUUAUUUAAAUAAGUGCCUUUAUUUCCUAGUGUCUCAACUCUUGAAAACUUAGAAUAAGAUUAACCUAUUUUCGUUUCACACUUUCCCCUCUCUUUUGGGGUUCCUUCCCUUUUUCUUCUAAGUGAAUAAUACUUCCCAGGAUGAUCCUUGUAUGGAUUUACCUACAUCGACAGUUCAGAAUAAGUCCGAAGGGCUGUAUGCAUAGGUGUCUUUUGUUCAUUUUUUGUGAUCCUCCUAGUGUAGAUAAGUAAGGAACUGGAAGCAAGCUGUGUGUGUGUUUUUUGUUUGUUUGUUUUGUUUUUUGGUAAGUUUGCAUCCUCUGGACGACUUUUUCAAGGCCUCCCUUUUUUAUAUGGCUGUAGACUCCUGGCAUUUUAAUCAGACUAAAGCCCUUGGUAGAAGGCAUUUUGUCCAUGUUCAUAUCUGUUGUGUGGAAUCUGAAGAUAGCAAUGUGAGAUUUUAAAUGAUCACUUUGAACAAGGAUCUCUGUUUGCCUUGCACUUAUGGAAACUGAGGUGCACAGAAAUAUCCUGCUUUUCUAACCUACAUGGUGAUGCCUAAGCCAGGUUACAGUGAUUAUACUAACUGAUUCUUGAUGUUGUCCUCACAAACAGAUCAUAUUCUUAAUUUCCAGCUCUAACAUAAAGGAAUAUACACUGUUUGUGAGUGGCUUAAAGGAUUUGCCCAGCUGUGAGGAAGUAGACAGGACUGUAGAGCAAGUCAGGAGACCUGGGUUCUAAUUCUGGCUCUCACGCUCACUUAGGAUGUGAUGUGGGUGAGUCUCUUCAUCUCCACCCUGUAGCUGGCUCAGUUUCCUAAUCUACAGAACAUCUACAGAAUGAGAGACAGGGAGGGAGCAGGUGAUCUUCAAGGUGCUUUAGAGUUAACAUUGUCAUAUCUACAUGGUGUAUAACUUUGAACUUGUAUGUGGCAGAGGAGGUUUAGAGAUAUUAUCAUUCUUAUUUAAUAUGUUCCUUUUAAUAUAGGAAGUUUAUUUGUCAUUGCUUUUGAGACUUGGCCAUCACCCUUAAGAGGGCUCUUGAUGGUGCUGUUGUGCAGAAUGGAAGCUGACUUUAAGAAGGUCUUUAAUGAUCAUCAGAGCAUAUUUAUAUACUACUCUCUUGUAUGUGACCUGUGCCUAAUGUAGCUUUACUCCCAAGGUGACUCCUAGACUUGGAACUGGAAGGAAUCUAAUCCAUCCCCUUCAUUUUAUGUGCAAAGCAUAAAAACAAUAGCAAAUGCCUGUUUCAUGGAUUUUAUGUGCCAGGGACUCUUCUAAAUGCUUUACAUAUAUUAACUCACUCAAUCCUCCCAAUAGUCUUGAAGUACAUUCUCUAUUUAAAUAACUAAGGAGCAGAGAAGUAAUUUGCUUAGAAUUAUACACCAUAAAGUGACAGAGCCAGGACUGGAACCCAGGCAACUUGCCUGUACUAGGGAUAUGGUUCAAGUUAGCCCAGCUAUCUAGCACCGGGCUUUUCUGUCAUCAGUGACCUAAAAUGUUUCACUAAAAGGAAAAGAUCCUAAUAAACCAUCUAUUGUGUGUUUCUUCUAGUUUUAUGAAGAGUAAUUUUGAGAGUUGCUUCAGUAAUGUGAUUGCACAGGAUGAAUUAAAUGAACACCAAAGCUUUUGUAAUUGAACUGAGUGACCCAGGAAGAGCUGAAUAGCAGUUAACUGACCUUAGACACAUCUAUUCAUGGACUCCUUUUUAGUUUGCAGUGCUGCACGAUGCAUUGUAAAACUAGUCUGUGUGCAUACACAUGCGUUAUUUCUGCUUACCUCUCAUAUGUGGGAAGCUGAACAUUUUAGGGAUUAAGAAAUCUGCCUCCAUUGUUGUUUAGAAGCCUCUGCUCCUUGCCUGGCACUACUGGCUGUUGGGAAUGUGAAGAUAAAUAAGAGUGACUACCCUUGACUGGUUCACAGUUUGUUCCAGAGACAGAUAAUGAGGCAACAGUUCCAGUACAGUGUGAAUCCUGCUGCGAUAGGAACACAAAUGCAGCUUUGAGCUCCUGCAGCUUGUACUUCUUCAGGGGCUUAUUCUCUUGUCCUGUAAGUAGUACACUUUUGAGGUAAGGUGAAGACAACAGCACUGUUGCUUGCUCGGUUUGUGUUUUGUUUGUUUCUUUUGCGAUUGGCAUAACGGAACAAAGAAAUAAAAGAUGUAGUUCUGAGGUUAUGCAGUUGAGUGGCCCGGCUGGGAGCAGCCCUCUCCAACCAAAUCAGGCCUUUCUUUCCUCAAACAAGAUAAUCUCAAAACAUAACCUGGUGGUUUUAUAUGUCUUCACUGUGGAGAUGUUUUGUGCUGUUCCUCUUUUUGUUUAUAACCUAUUUUUCCUUUCAAUAGACUUGGUUCUUUUUUUUUUUUUUUUUUUUUUUGAGACAGGGUCUCGCUUUGUUGCCCAGACUGGGGUGCAGUGGCAUGAACACGGCUCACUGCAGCCUCAGCCUCCUGGGCUCAAGCGAUCCUCCCACCUCAGCCUUCUGAGUAGCUAGGACUACAGGCAUGCAUCACCACGCAUGGCUAAUUUUUUAAUUUUUGUAGAGACAGAGUCUUGCUGUGUUGCCCAGGGUGGUCUUGAACUCCUGGGCUCAACCAAUCUUCCUGUCUUGGCCUCCCAAAGUCUUGGUUCUUUUCACUAGGACAUUCUCUUCCUCCACCAAAUUAUGGAGAUAAGAACUUUGUUUAUAACCUUAAAAUUUUCUCAGUAGUCAGUGGUGUUAACAUUGGGCCACUACACAAUUACACACACUAUUCUUGAGAAUGUCUAGGAGUGUUUUAUUAGGUAAUACCCAGUUUCUUUAAGGUAAAGGAGUGAUAGGGAGCUGAGGCUGUGUGCAUAGGGUGCUUGGAUUUGUUUCUCUGGCCGAGCAUACCCUUAAAAGUGUCGGGCAGUAGAAAAUGGAUGGAAUUCCACUCCUGAAUCUGCUACUGUUACUUUUGGCAAGUUACUCAAUCUCUCUGAGGUUGUGUUUGGAGGUAUGUAAAAUAAAAAUAAAAAUAGCUAUUUAGUUGAGUUGUUAGGAAGAACAAGUAACAUAUGUAAAGUGUCUCCAUGCUGGCAUGCCAUAGUAACCCCAUAAAUGAUUGCUGUUGUUAUCUUUGUAAGUGAGAUAUACCAGUGUCUUUCUGACCGUGUCUUUCUGACCGUGGGAUUUUGAGCUACUGGUGUGCCUUUGCUUUAUUCUUGGUCUCAUUCCUUCUUUAUGUCUCAGAAUAUCUCUGUUGUUCCAAACCAAAGUUUGAGCAGACACAGUAUAGUAAAUGAGGAUAGCCAGUGUCCAAGGUAGCUGGUUAUAUUUUUUCCAGAGGUGAUCACUGCCAAGUUAAAUUAAAAAGGGAAGACCAGAGUUUCCCUGUCAGUUCUAAUGGGCAUCACAGUUGCAUUUCCACGAUAUAAGGAAAAAGGACACUUGUGAUGUAGUUCUCUGGCAGGUAUUGUGGGCGGGAACAUGGUAGUAGCAUCCAGCUCCAGUCUGCCCCUGUCCUGCCUCCAGUCAGGGCUGUACGCUGUGGACCAAAGAUCAUGCUCGCUGAUGAGAGCCACCCUGCUGGUGACCUCAGUGCUGCCGACCCAUUUACAUCCCAGCCCUGCCACAUUCCUACAGUGGGAGGUUGAACACAUUUCUUAACCUUGAUGAGCCUCAGUUUCAUCAUCAGUAAAAUGAAGUUAAUGGAACCAUGGAAUCUACCUUGGAGAGUUGCUAGAAGAAUUAAAUGAAGUCACAUAUGUUUAGUGCCCAGCACAGCGUCCAGCACAUAGGUGGUACAGAGUAAGUGGUAAUUUUAGUUUUCUUUCUACCCUCUUUGUGGAGGACAUUCAUGCAAACCCUCUCUUUCCCUUUUUACCUCUUUUCUUCCAGUCUGUUUUUAUCCCUUAGAGUAUUAAAUGCAAUAAACAGGAUUUGGCUAAAUGGACAUAGUAGUAUUUUUGAAAAAACUAGCCACAAUCCAGUUAUAUCACUUCUCAUUCUCCUGAAUCAGUGUGUUUAACCUACUGGUUGACAUCCAUUAGUAGAUUAUGAAAUCCAGUGGGUCACAACCACAAUUUUUGUUUAUAAAUGGAAUAGACUAAAAUAGGAAAAAGCCACAAUGUGUAUGCAUAUUAUCGAUAAAUAUUGUUUGGGAAAACCUUUGUUCAGGUCCUGAUGUAUUUCAUACUGUGAUUAUGAAUUUUUGAAAGUUCAGAGAGCUCUUCUAACACAAAUUAUACACUGUACAAAUUCUGUGUUGUUUUUCUUUCACUGAGAGCUUUUUUAAACAUGAUGUUACAAUUUCCUUAUUCAUUAUUGCACAGUGGCUCUUCUAUGGAUAAGCAUUGGUACUGAAGACAGUACAUUAGUCCUGGUGUUUUUAGCCCGGAAGACUGGGCAAAGCGGGAUAAGCAUGCAUUGCUGUGAAGCGCAUCAGAGUUUUGGAGCAGAGUCUGGGUAGAGCAUGUGUGGUGGGAGGUAAUGAUCCCAAUGCAUAGGUUCUUAUUCUAGUUUUUUGAGGGUGCUUUGGGGUCAGUUACUGUUCCUUUACCUGAAAUAAGUUAGAAAAAGAAAAGGAGGAAUUGCAAUUUAUUUGCAGGGAAAUAAUGAGCCUUAGUGAGUUGUAUUUGGUAAAGUGCUUUGAUAUCACCUCAAAGGCAUUCCUGAAAUUAUUCUUCAUUCUAUGCCUAAUGGGUUAUAUUUUGAAGUUGUGAUCCAAUUAUUGCUAACAUAGUACUUUAAAUUCCCACUGUGCUGGGCACAUUAACGAAAAUCCCUUGAGUAGAUCUGCCUCUGUGCACCUUAAUUCUUGUUCGUACACCAUCCAGUAUGUAAAUAUUUCUCUAGUGCUUUUUGUGUUCUGAGCACCGUGGAUGAAAAUGAUAGGAAAUGCCUUUCAGCUUAUGACUUUGCUCAGCUGCUCUCUGAGCACUGAGGAGUUUGUCUUCCUAAAAACGGUAAACUAGCAUUCUUAUUAAGUUGCUAUUUGAGUUUUAUGUCCAGAGCUGCUGCUGGUGGGCCCAGGGGUUGUGAAAUUUCUUGGCCGUGAGUUUGAAAAUGGUUGAAUAAAAUAUAAUUAAAAACAAGCAGGCCAGGUGCGGUGGCUCACACCUGUAAUCCUAGCAUUUUGGGAGGCCAUGGUGGGUGGAUCACCUGAGGUCAAGAGUUUGAGACCAGCCUAGCCAACAUGGUGAAACCCUGUCUCUACUAAAAAUACAAAAAAUUAGCCAGGUGUGGUGGUGGGUGCCUGUAAUCCCAGCUACUCAGGAGGCUGAGGCAAGAGAAUCCCUUGAGCCCGGGAAGCAGAGGUUGCAGUGAGCCGAGAUCGCACCAUUGCACUCCAGCCUGGGCAACAAGAGCGAAACUCCAUCUCAAAAAAAGAAAGAAAGAAAGAAAAAGAAACAAGGAAAUCGUAGUACCAUAAGAGGAAAGAAUGACACACUCCUACACUCCUGCAAGACAUCCAAGAUUACAAAAAACCAGACUGCUGGUUCCUGCUGGGAUGAUCACACUACAGCUGUGCUAGAUGACCACACCCCAGACUCGCUCUUUACUGAGCGUGUUUGAAGAAGAUGCUGGCACCCUCACAGACUAUACCAACCAGCUGCUCCAGGCAAUGCAGCGCGUCUAUGGAGCCCAGAAUGAGAUGUGCCUGGCCACACAACAGCUUUCUAAGCAACUGCUGGCAUAUGAAAAACAGAACUUUGCUCUUGGCAAAGGUGAUGAAGAAGUAAUUUCAACACUCCACUAUUUUUCCAAAGUGGUGGAUGAGCUUAAUCUUCUCCAUACAGAGCUGGCUAAACAGUUGGCAGACACAAUGGUUCUACCUAUCAUACAAUUCCGAGAAAAGGAUCUCACAGAAGUAAGCACUUUAAAGGAUCUAUUUGGACUCGCUAGCAAUGAGCAUGACCUCUCAAUGGCAAAAUACAGCAGGCUGCCUAAGAAAAAGGAGAAUGAGAAGGUGAAGACCGAAGUCGGAAAAGAGGUGGCCGCGGCCCGGCGGAAGCAGCACCUCUCCUCCCUUCAGUACUACUGUGCCCUCAACGCGCUGCAGUACAGAAAGCAAAUGGCCAUGAUGGAGCCCAUGAUAGGCUUUGCCCAUGGACAGAUUAACUUUUUUAAGAAGGGAGCAGAGAUGUUUUCCAAACGUAUGGACAGCUUUUUAUCCUCCGUUGCAGACAUGGUUCAAAGCAUUCAGGUAGAACUGGAAGCCGAGGCGGAAAAGAUGCGGGUGUCCCAGCAAGAAUUACUUUCUGUUGAUGAAUCUGUUUACACUCCAGACUCUGAUGUGGCCGCACCACAGAUCAACAGGAACCUCAUCCAGAAGGCUGGUUACCUUAAUCUUAGAAACAAAACAGGGCUGGUCACCACCACCUGGGAGAGGCUUUAUUUCUUCACCCAAGGCGGGAAUCUCAUGUGUCAGCCCAGGGGAGCCGUGGCUGGAGGUUUGAUCCAGGACCUGGACAACUGCUCAGUGAUGGCCGUGGAUUGCGAAGACCGGCGCUACUGCUUCCAGAUCACCACGCCCAAUGGAAAAUCGGGAAUAAUCCUCCAGGCUGAGAGCAGAAAGGAAAAUGAAGAGUGGAUAUGUGCAAUAAACAACAUCUCCAGACAGAUCUACCUGACCGACAACCCUGAGGCAGUCGCGAUCAAGUUGAAUCAGACCGCUCUGCAAGCAGUGACUCCCAUUACAAGUUUUGGAAAAAAACAAGAAAGCUCAUGCCCCAGCCAGAACCUGAAAAAUUCAGAGAUGGAAAAUGAAAAUGACAAGAUUGUUCCCAAAGCAACAGCCAGUCUACCUGAAGCAGAGGAGCUGAUCGCGCCUGGAACGCCGAUUCAAUUCGAUAUUGUGCUUCCUGCUACAGAAUUCCUUGAUCAGAACAGAGGGAGCAGGCGUACCAACCCUUUUGGUGAAACUGAGGAUGAAUCAUUUCCAGAAGCAGAAGAUUCUCUUUUGCAGCAGAUGUUUAUAGUUCGGUUUUUGGGAUCAAUGGCAGUUAAAACAGACAGCACUACUGAAGUGAUUUAUGAAGCGAUGAGACAAGUAUUGGCUGCUCGGGCUAUUCAUAACAUCUUCCGCAUGACAGAAUCCCAUCUGAUGGUCACCAGUCAAUCUUUGAGGUUGAUAGAUCCACAGACUCAAGUAUCAAGGGCCAAUUUUGAACUUACCAGUGUCACACAAUUUGCUGCUCAUCAAGAAAACAAGAGACUGGUUGGUUUUGUCAUCCGUGUUCCUGAAUCCACUGGAGAAGAAUCUCUGAGUACAUACAUUUUUGAAAGCAACUCAGAAGGCGAAAAGAUAUGUUAUGCUAUUAAUUUGGGAAAAGAAAUUAUUGAGGUUCAGAAGGAUCCAGAAGCACUGGCUCAAUUAAUGCUGUCCAUACCACUAACCAAUGACGGAAAAUAUGUACUGUUAAACGAUCAACCAGAUGACGAUGAUGGAAAUCCAAACGAACAUAGAGGCGCAGAAUCCGAAGCAUAACUCACUUGCGCCUGUGGGGGAAGAGCAAACAGGAAGGAGAGCUACCUCCUAAGGGUUUUAACGUCUCUGACAUACAGGCACACUGACCUGAUUUCCGAAGGCUGACAAUCGUUUGUGGAAUGUAAUCUUGAUGCCUUGAUACUGAGACUUGGGAGGGAAACUAAGAAAUGGUUGACAGCGUUCCCACCCAUCUACAAUGUUAUUUUAGGUGCUUUGUGGUAAGUCUUUUUUCUUAGAUUGCGCUAAAAUUUCUUAGAUUGUUCAGCGCUCAGAACAAAAGUUUGAAAAAUGCAUUGUUCAUAUGAAUGUCAUCUCUUUUCAGUUUCCAGUAUCCUUUUUAAAAAAUGGCAAAAGCCUAGAUUUACAAUUUGAUGAACACUAAAUAUUUCUUAUUAAUAUAAUCUAUUUUUGUAUUUUACUUAAUGAGCUUUAAGUGCCUGUCGUUCUGAAAAUUGUGUAUUUAUAAUUCAGCUUAUCUCAUAAUUGGACCUAAUAGCAUUUCUUUGUGCAGUUAGGUGAUGAGCACUGCUUUGAGGCCCAAGCACUAGUAGAGAUGCGCGAUACAGGUCUAGUUUCGGUAACUGUUCCAGACAUCAAGCAAUAAAAAAAUGAAUACCACAAAAGAUGUUUGAUUUUACAGUGGAGCCUUACUGAACCAGCAUUCAGAAGUUUAAGGUCCUCCUAGGUAUGAGUAUUUUUAGUAGUGGAUCACUGUGGACAGGGUGCAGCUCUACCAGUUCCUGUUUCUUCUGAGCCAGACCCUCUUCAGGGAAGGGACCAAUUAAUUUUAAAACUCACUUGAAGCACAGCUGGUCAUGGGGCUUGGUAUAAAGUUCCUAUUUCCACCCUGAUACUUCCAAUUCCUGGAACCCCAGCCCACUCCCCCAUCCCUCCUCCCUAUCAAACUAGUAUAAUGAUUUUGAAUCGGUACAGUGUGUUUAACUGUAACUAAGUUCAACAGACUAUUAUUAUCUUUGUAAUAAAUUAACCUAGCAAUAAAAAAUAUUCUGUUUC